GAGUUCCGAGCGACCGAUGGAGAUGGCGGCUGCGGCUGAGUGACGGACGGUGGAGGCCCAGAGCCCGGGCCUGAAGGGGGGGACAAACCUGGGUGCCCGCAGGAGCCCGGCAGGGUACAUACAGAGGGUACUGUGCUAAACCCUGGGGAGACGGCGAAGUGGAAAACAUAUAGAGUCUGUGCCCUCCCAGAUUUUACAGUCUUACUUGGUCACUUCACGUAUGUACCUGCGGUUAUAAAUUGAGAUGAGUGCUGUGAAGGAGAAGUCCAUUCUGAUGCUCUGAGUGUCUUACAAGUAUCAAGAACUUACUAUAUGUGGUUGAAUAAACAAUCAAGGUAAAGAGCAUCAAGUAAAAACUUCUGCUUGUUGAUAAGUACUUCAGACAUUCCCCCAGUGGCUGAAGUGGCAUAUGAAUUAUGAAGUUGGAUCAUUUGGAAUGAAUGUAAGAGAAUUGCCAAGGGCUCCUCCUACUCCAGAGAGGAAACCUCAUCCAGGGCCAUGAAGCCACUUCCUCACCAUCUGUGUGCUGCUUAAGCUAAUGCUGCGGGAACCAUGGUUCCUUGGGAGGAAUCAAGCUGACUCUUGGCAUGAGAUUCCUGCCUUCCUAGGGUUGAGAGCGGCACUGCCAUGGCUUCUCUGGACGACCCAGGGGAAGUGAGGGAGGGCUUCCUCUGCCCUCUGUGCCUGAAGGAUCUGCAGUCUUUCUAUCAGCUUCACUCACAUUACGAGGAAGAACACUCAGGGGAAGACCGUGAUGUCAAAGGGCAAAUUAAAAGUCUUGUCCAGAAGGCUAAAAAAGCAAAGGACAGGUUGUUGAAACGAGAAGGGGAUGAUCGAGCAGAGUCAGGGACCCAAGGAUAUGAGUCUUUCAGCUAUGGAGGGGUUGAUCCUUACAUGUGGGAACCCCAGGAGCUUGGUGCUGUGAGAAGCCAUCUUUCCGACUUCAAAAAACACCGAGCUGCUAGAAUUGACCACUAUGUUGUGGAAGUCAAUAAACUAAUAAUCAGGUUAGAGAAGCUCACUGCAUUUGACAGAACAAAUACUGAGUCUGCAAAGAUUCGAGCAAUAGAAAAGUCUGUGGUGCCUUGGGUCAACGACCAGGAUGUCCCUUUCUGUCCAGACUGUGGGAAUAAGUUCAGCAUCCGGAACCGCCGCCACCACUGCCGCCUCUGCGGGUCUAUUAUGUGCAAGAAGUGUAUGGAGCUCAUCAGCCUUCCCUUGGCAAACAAGCUCACCAGUGCCAGCAAGGAGUCCCUGAGCACCCACACCAGCCCCAGCCAGUCACCCAACAGUGUCCAUGGCUCCCGCCGAGGCAGCAUCAGCAGCAUGAGCAGUGUCAGCUCGGUCCUGGAUGAGAAGGACGAUGACCGGAUCCGCUGCUGUACACACUGCAAGGACACGCUGCUCAAGAGAGAGCAGCAGAUUGAUGAGAAGGAGCACACACCUGACAUCGUGAAGCUCUACGAGAAAUUACGACUUUGCAUGGAGAAAGUUGACCAGAAAGCUCCAGAAUACAUCAGGAUGGCAGCAUCAUUAAAUGCUGGGGAGACAACCUACAGUCUGGAACAUGCCAGUGACCUUCGAGUGGAAGUGCAGAAAGUGUAUGAGCUGAUAGACGCUUUAAGUAAGAAGAUCUUAACCUUGGGCUUGAACCAGGACCCUCCACCACAUCCAAGCAAUUUGCGGCUGCAGAGAAUGAUCAGAUACUCAGCUACACUUUUUGUGCAGGAAAAGUUGCUUGGUUUGAUGUCACUGCCAACCAAAGAACAGUUUGAGGAACUGAAAAAGAAAAGGAAGGAGGAAAUGGAGAGGAAGAGGGCCGUGGAGAGACAAGCUGCCCUGGAGUCCCAGCGAAGGCUUGAGGAAAGGCAGAGUGGCCUGGCUUCUCGAGCGGCCAACGGGGAGGUGGCAUCUCUCCGCAGGGGCCCUGCCCCCUUGAGAAAGGCUGAGGGCUGGCUCCCACUGUCAGGAGGUCAGGGGCAGAGUGAGGACUCAGACCCGCUCCUCCAGCAGAUCCACAACAUCACAUCAUUCAUCAGGCAGGCCAAGGCCGCGGGCCGCAUGGAUGAAGUGCGCACUCUGCAGGAGAACCUGCGGCAGCUGCAGGACGAGUAUGACCAGCAGCAGACAGAGAAGGCCAUCGAGCUGUCCCGGAGGCAGGCUGAGGAGGAGGACCUGCAGCGGGAACAGCUGCAGAUGUUGCGUGAACGGGAGUUGGAACGAGAAAGGGAGCAGUUUCGGGUGGCAUCCCUGCACACACGGACUCGGUCCCUGGACUUCAGAGAAAUCGGCCCUUUUCAGCUGGAGCCCAGCAGAGAGCCUCGCACCCACCUUGCUUAUGCUUUGGAUCUAGGCUCUUCCCCAGUUCCAAGCAGCACAGCUCCCAAGACCCCUUCACUUAGCUCAACUCAACCCACCAGAGUGUGGUCUGGGCCCCCAGCCGUUGGCCAGGAGCGCUUACCCCAGAGCAGCAUGCCACAGCAACAUGAGGGGCCCUCCUUAAACCCCUUUGAUGAGGAAGACCUCUCCAGCCCCAUGGAAGAGGCCACUACUGGUCCUCCUGCUGCAGGGGUUUCCUUAGACCCUUCAGCCCGCAUCCUGAAAGAGUACAAUCCUUUCGAGGAAGAGGACGAGGAGGAGGAAGCAGUGGCAGGGAAUCCAUUCAUUCAGCCAGACAGCCCAGCUCCUAACCCCUUCAGUGAGGAAGACGAACAUCCCCAGCAGAGGCUCUCAAGCCCUCUGGUUCCUGGUAACCCCUUUGAGGAACCCACCUGUAUCAACCCCUUUGAGAUGGACAGUGACAGUGGGCCAGAGGCUGAGGAGCCCAUAGAGGAAGAGCUCCUCCUGCAGCAGAUCGAUAACAUCAAGGCAUACAUCUUUGAUGCCAAGCAGUGCGGCCGCCUGGAUGAGGUAGAGGUGCUGACAGAGAAUCUGCGGGAGCUGAAGCACACCCUGGCCAAGCAGAAGGGGGGCACUGACUGACCAGCAGUGGAGAGGGCACCUUUGGGCCCAGGGGUCUGGCAGGAGCCAGUGGAGCAGGACAGAGGGCAGGCAGGAUGGAUGGGGAAGGUGGCAGGGUGAGAACUCAGAUGCACACAGGUGAGGGGCAGGAAUCUGCUGUUUUGUGUUGCGCACUUUGAGGUAUUUCCACUACAGUUGAAUAAUAAAAUAGAAACUAGAACAGGGAGAAUCAGCAUUCAGUUGCUGCUUUUCCUGUUUAUUAUUACUAUCUUUUGUAAUCGGAGGUUUACCCCUUUUGAAGGGACUUUACAUUUUUACUACCGAGAUAUAACUAAAUGCAGCUCUGUUGGGCCCAGGGCAGAAAUGGCUGCUGUGUACCUCUUGGGUCCAUUUGCUACUGCCUAGUCUUGGUUCCUUAUGCAGUAUUAUAGGGCAGCCUUUUUAGAGCCCUUCCUUUAGCCAAGACAGAGAAGAUAGAUUCCACUGAGCUCUAUUCUGCUCUGACAGAAGUCCAUCCCUAGUAGGCUGUGAGUUCCAUUUCACCUGGGGCCGCCUCUCCCCUGCUCUGCACUUCCUGUCUGUACAAUAGAAGGGGGAGGUGCUGCUAUGAAGGGGAGAGUUUAGACCCAGGAGAGCCCAGCACCUCUUUUUAAGGUGGGGUGAUGGGAAUAUUUCACCAGGGUCUAUUUUCUCAGUUUAAGUUCUUUUUUGUCUCUUUCAGGAAGUUAAGCUCCCAGUGCAGGGUAUCAAUGUGAAUCUGGUCCUGAGCUUUUUAGAAAAUAAGAGUGGUGGCCGGGCGCGCUGGCUCACGCCUGUAAUCGCAACACUUUGGGAGGCCGAGGCAGGCAGAUCACAAGGUCAGGAGAUCGAGACCACCCUGGCUAACACAGUGAAAUCCCGUCUCUACUAAAAAUACAAAAAAUUAGCCAGGCGUGGUGGUGGGUGCCUGUAGUCCCAGCUACUUUGGAGGCUGAGGCAGGAGAAUGCUGUGAACCCGGGAGGCAGAGCUUGCAGUGAGCCGAGAUCGCACCACUGCACUCCAGCCUGGGCAGUGAGAGUGAGACUCCGUCUCAAAAAAAAAUAAGAGUGGUUAACUUUUUGGUUGAUAUUAGUAUUAUUUGUGAGAAGAGUUUCCCCACCCUUCUUCUGAUAGAACAAUUGUCUGUCACUGGAGAAAUCUCCCUCCAGAGCUUUGGCAAAGUUACUCUGAUCUGGGUCUGUUUAAAAGGCCGGGUCUCUAAUUUAGGAAUCGGUGAUUUGGAAGCUUUUGCAGAACAUCACCAGAAGAAGGGAAGCUUCCCAGAGUCAGAAGCUAAAUUAAAAUAAUUUCCAAGGCUAUUUGAUCAGCCUUCUUCCUUUUUGGUUCAUUGUGUCCUGACUUGGGGCACUGAUGAGAUUUUUUAUUUUUUUUGAGACAGAGUUUCACUUUGUUGCCCAGGCUGGAGUGUAGUGGCAUGAUCUCAGCUCACUGCAACCUCCACCUCCCUGGUUCAAGUGAUAUUUGUGCCUCAGCCCCCUGAAUAGCUAGGAUUACAGGCGUGGGCCACCACGCCUGGUUAAUCUCUGUAUUUUUAGUAGAGGUAGAGUUUCACCAUUUUGGCCAGGCUGGUUUCGAACUCCUGGCCUCAAGUGAUCUGCCACCUUGGCCUCCCAAAGUGCUGGGAAUACAGGCGUGAGCCACUGUGCCCGCCCUGAUGAGAUAUUUUAUUACCAAUGUUAGUAUUGAGAAACUGAAAUGUUUGAAGAAGCACAACCCAGGAUCGUGCUGGUAGCACCACAGUACUUAAACUGUUGGUCAAUUAAGGCCAGAAAGGGAAAUUGUUAAUUUAGCUCUGGUGCUUUGGUUUACAGGAACAUAACUCUUAACUGACAUCUGACAUCAUGAUAGCCAUAUGUGCUCAGCUCUGGGUAGAGUUUCUGCAGUUACUCAUCUGAACUAAUGAACAAUAACUGACCACUAGUCACUUUAUGCCGUGUAACUAGCUCUAGGCCAUACUUUCACUGGUUACUGGUGUGAAAGCUGAAAUUCAUUUUGUUACAUUCUGGUGAAGACCCCUCUUGAUAAUGGGAAUGUUUUAACUCUCUUGAUGAAAAAAUAAUCUGUAUUUGUGUUGAUGUUCACAUUUCUGUAGCACAUUUCUUAUCCUUUUGGUUGAAUGAAAAGAUCUUGUAUAGGGGUGUGGAGAUGGGGAGUGGGUAGAAGUGUGUGAAGGACGCUUUGCAUUUGGGAUCUGUUCACAAACAGCCAUAUGAGUGUGUUAAUGAAUGUCAGCCAGUUACCAACCCUGCUGGUUGUUAUGGGUUGUUUUGAGAAGUUGGCAACCAGGCAUCUAAGAUGUUGCCUGGUACAGGCCUCUUUUCUUCCCUGAGGCCCAUGACAUUUCUCUGUUACUCUAGAGGGUUUCUCAGAUGGCCAGUAGGCUCCUCCCUGCUUAGGGUCUCAUUUCUCUGAAAAGAGGAUGAACUGAAAAGCAGGUAGUUCCAGAAGCUAAUUGCUGCUUUCCAUCAUAAUUAUUUUUCUUGUGAGAACAUUUCUCUUUUAAUUAGCUAGUGAUUUUGAUUAAGACUAAUUCACUAAACAUACCCUUCCCUCAAAUCACCUCAGGUAGCAAUCUGUAAGUAACUAAAAGCAUUGAAAAACACACAAGAAACAUUUUUAAAAACUAUUUUUAAAGGCCUGGCCGGGUGCAGUGGCUCACUCCUGUAAUCCCAGCACUUUGGGAGGCCGAGACGGGUGGAUCACCUGAGGUCAGGAAUUUGAGACUAGCAUGGCCAACAUGGUGAAACCCCGUGUCUACUAAAAAUACAAAAAUUAGCUGGGCGUGGUGGCAGACGCCUGUAAUCCCAGCUACUCAGGGAGGCUGAGGCACGAGAAUCGCUUGAACCUGGGAGGCGGAGGUUGCAGUGAGCCAAGAUUGCGCCACUGCACUCCAACCUGGGUGACAAGAGCAAGACUCCGUCUCACAAAAAACAAACAAAACUGACUGAUUGAAUAUACUAAACCAAACUAAAAUCAUAUUCUUUUGAUUAAGUUUAUCCAUGGCUGUAUUCUUCUAUGAAUUCUUCCAUUUAAUUCUUCCACGAUUAUCUUCUCCUGUAAAUACAUCACAGGAGUUAGAAUUCUCUACCCAUCAGCUGUACCAUGUCGCAGAAUUCAUGCAGGCACAAAGUUGGAGUUACAGAGAUGGGUUGACAGCAGGCAAACUUGGCCUAUGUAUUAUAACCACAACUUCAAGUUCUUACCUCAUGUGAAUAUUCACCCUUUCUUUAGUCUUCCAAGGCAAACAGCCCCGUCUCAUCACCAGAUGAGCAAGGUCUUGAUAUGGCAUAGCAGAUCUCCCUAGACACAGAUCAUGAGAAAAGAUGGAAGAGACUUAGGGAUUCAGGCAUCAGAUGAAGUUGGCUUUUCCCUUUUAUGCCUUGUUUGUAUUUACCCUGUCUAAUACACUAAGGAUACUUACUCAUUGUACUUGCAGCUCAAUAUGUCUUUGCUGUUCAGAUACUAAAAUGUACCUCUGAGUCAUUGUGAGCUGUGUGGUAGGUUGGACAUUGGCAUAGUUGGUGAUGGGACUCAAAAUGAAAAGGUGGUCUCUUUACCAGGUCACAGACUGUAGCAGAUUGUGCUUGUUAUCUGACAAUGACUGUCACUUUGAGGGUCGUUGAUUUGCAUGCACUACUCUGGGGCCUUGUAUUGGAGCCUUUUUUAAAAAAAAUAAAAUCUGAGAUAGAG